CAGGUGCCUCAGGAGCCCGUUGGAGACAUUGGCAUUAACUUAUGGCUUCCUAGAAGAAGAGGACUUGAAAUGCCUGCCCCGGUACCCAAGUCUCAGUCAACUGAAGCAGCUGAAUCUGAGUCAUGGUGCACUGCGCUUCAUCCGUCUUGAGCCCCUCCGAGCUCUGCUAGAGAAAGUUGCUGCCACUCUUCAGACCCUCUUCUUAGUGGACUGUGGGAUUGGGUACUCCAAACUCAGGGUCAUCCUGCCUGCCCUGAGCCGCUGCUCCAACCUCACCACUUUCUGUUUUCACGGCAAUGACACGUCCAUGGAUGCUCUGAAGGACCUGCUGCGCCACACAGGCAGGCUGAGCAAUUUGAGCCUGGAAACAUAUCCUGCCCCUCGGGAGAGUCUUGACAACAGGGGUCGUGUCAUUUUGGAGCUCCUCACCCCACUUCAGGCUGAGCUGAUGCGUAUACUGAGGGAAGUAAGGGAGCCCAAAAGGAUCUUCUUUGGUCCGGUGUCCUGCCCUUGCUGUGGCACUUCGCCCACUGAGCAACUGGAGUUCAAUUUUUGCUUGUGGGGAAGGCCUGCCUAG